GUUGUUUACCAGCAGGACAGAGCCCGGGCGCAGGCGGCGGAUGGAGCGGAACGGCUAGGUGAGAGCGGCUGCCCGAUCCCGCGGCCUGCCCUUGGCCUCCGCCAGGCCUGGAAGGGGCCGGGGGAGGCCAGUCCCCGAGACCCCAGCACAUCACCCGGGAGGGCCUCCCCAGACCCAGCCCGGGGGACGCAAACCCCGGGAGACAGGCGAGGAGCCUGGAGAAAAGUCUGCUCCCGAGGCAAAGCAAGCCUGGCCAGAGCUCACCUUUACCAAAAUAGGGUGACUCCCGGGCUCUGCAGAAACCGAGGGACCUAUGCAACCGCUGGGCCAUGCCCUCCAGGCUGGGAUGUAGCGACGGGGACACAGACCCAGGGAGAGAAAAGGAUGUCCCAGUCUCCGGCAGGGCAGAGACGAGAACCAGAGGGCCCCUCCCCCAGUCCUGUGCUCUUUCUCUGAAGUCAAUUCUCGCUUUCUAAACGCUCUUUCUCGCCCCUCCCCCAGAUCCCUCCUCUGCCUCUUAAGCCUGUUGCCUUCUAGGGCGCUGGAACUUGGACUUAAUUGAGUUAUCCCCACCACCUCCCUGCCCUUCUGACGCUGGAAUCAUCCCCAGUUCUCUAUCCAAACAUUUGAUCACUUGGUGGCUUGUGGUUCAGUGUGGCACUCUGCAUAGGACAGUGUAUUCUAAUCCCUAGUUUGGGGUAGAACUGGGAAUGGUACCAGAGUUUUUUCAUUCUCAGGCCAACCACCAUCUCCUGUUGGUUCUUCAGAGCAUUUUUAUCCUGAAAGCCUGGUGGGGGUGUGGGUUGGGGGGGGCGGGAUGGCAACGGAUAGGAUUAACUGAUACAGUUUUAAAAGACCAAUUCAAAUGUAUGUAUCUUGGUAUAUACCAGCAGAUGGUAUGUAGGUGGUUAUAUUUUACUGCAUAUACUGUAGGCUUAGAUUUGGGUUGUGAGUGAAAUAGGGUGGUCUGACCCUGUGGUGGGUGGUGGGCACCCUUAGAAAGCAGGAGCCCUGCUUUAGCUUCUCCUAUCCACAUUUCCUUCUUUCCAGUUGAUUUGGUGGUGAAUCUUAAGGAAUGGGCACCUGCCCUUCUGGCAACUUCUUGGAAACAGUUGGCAGUGUUUGCUUCCUGACUCCUAGCAGGCCGCUGGGGUGCAGCUAUUGUGUUUAAGUAAACAGGCCACUCGCCUAUUCAGCUUGGCAGCUUGAUAGAUGCCUACGCCUAGAUCUUGUCAAAUCGGUUUGUGGUUGAGUGGCUGCCAGGCCUAGAGGUGGUGAAGUGAACUGAGCAGGGAGAAUCAUGGCUGCUGCCUCAAUCCUGGACUGAGGGUGGUGGGCAGAGUUCAGGACCUGAGGUGUGAAUAUAAAGGCACAGUUGGCCCAGAUCCCCAAACACCUGUUUCCCCCACCGCCCAUCCCUGUGUGAUGGGUGCUGGGGAGAGCUGGUGUUCCCUCCGUGUAACAGAUGGUCCCUGUGCUCGGGAGGAGGCAGUGGGUUAUGAAAGCAGGUUGGAUAUAAUGGUUUUACCUGAAGGAGGUGUUAGUCUCUAAAUAACCAUGAGUGGGCUCCUAGGAAUUAGUCAUAAUUGAGGUUUUUCUCUGAGAUAGCUCACAGUCAUGUUAUCUUAUGACCAGGGUGUCUUGAAUAUGACACCCCCUGAACAUGGAUAAUUAUAUGGAACCAAAAGGUAUAGAAAGUGCAUGCACAUACUCAAGUUUUACUGUUAAAAAUAAUCCCACAGAGAGCCUGUGAGAACACAUGACUCUCCUCAUCAAAGUUGUUAAGGAAGAGGUUUCUAAGUUACCAAACUCACUGACAGUUAAACCUUCCUGAGGCAUGUGUGGGUGUUGGAAGCCAAGCCUGUGAUAAUUCUGUAGAAGCUGUGGCAAAUUAAUAGCCAUUCCACAAGUGGGGAGGGUGGGCCGAGAGGGGCGUGGGUUUGCCUGUGGAGCUUAUCUUUGGCAGAACAGUUGGACAGUUAUGACCUUCUCCUGCCAUCCUGAGUGAAAGUGCAGAGCUGCUAAUUGCCAGAGAAAGACUUGAGAAGGAGACUAAAGGGGGAAAAACACAUUCUUCACAGUUGAUCAGAAAAUAGAUGAAAUUAACAAGGAGAUGGGCAGUCUUUUUUGAUGCCAAAAGUUUGCUAAGGAGAAGGCUCCUGAGCUACUAGCAGCCAGACUGGGUGUGAAAGACGAGGGAGAAGUGGAAAAUGGGAGUGGAGAGAGACUCAGGCUGUGAGUGGAAUGCAGCAGACAUAGAGGCCUUUAAAAGAGGGUAGCUUUGUCCAAGAUUUUGAAUUGAGCAGGACAUCAGGAAGAUAUAGGGAUAAUGUGUUGCGUUUGGUCCUGGUCUGAGUGGAGAGGAAGCAGAUACUCCUUAAAAUUAGGCAGCAGUGGUUACAUGUGCAGAAUGGUGAGGUUAGAAUACAAACCCUGAGAGGCUCAGAUUACAUUGUUCAAGAUUUUGUGAUGAAAGGAGUGAAUUUGCAGGAAGUGCAAAUCAUUCUGCAGGAAGUGAAUCUGAGGGGUCUUGAGAAGCAAUGGCCACAGAAGCCCCUGUGAAUAUAGCACCACCUGAGUGUAGCACUGUUGUCAGCACAGCAGUUGACAGCCUCAUUUGGCAGCCAAACUCACUAAAUAUGCACAUGAUAAGGCCCAAGUCCGCCAAGGGACGGACAAGACCGAGUCUGCAGAAAUCCCAGGGCGUGGAGGUGUGCGCUCAUCAUAUACCAUCUCCGCCUCCAGCCAUUCCCUAUGAGUUGCCAAGCAGCCAAAAACCAGGAGCCUGUGCACCCAAAUCUCCAAACCAGGGAGCUUCUGAUGAGAUCCCUGAGCUGCAGCAGCAAGUACCCACUGGGGCUUCCUCUUCUCUCAAUAAGUAUCCAGUCCUUCCUUCCAUCAACAGAAAGAACCUGGAGGAGGAGGCUGUGGAAACCGUUGCCAAAAAGGCCAGCUCACUGCAACUGAGCAGUAUCCGGGCUCUUUACCAAGACGAGACGGGCACCAUGAAGACAAGUGAAGAAGAUUCCAGAGCUCGAGCUUGUGCCGUGGAGAGGAAAUUCAUCGUCCGAACCAAGAAACAGGGCUCUUCCAGGGCUGGAAAUCUGGAGGAACCAUCGGACCAAGAACCAAGGUUGCUGCUUGCUGUUAGAUCACCAACAGGCCAAAGGUUUGUACGCCAUUUCCGGCCAACAGAUGAUUUGCAAACCAUUGUUGCUGUGGCCGAACAGAAAAACAAAACCUCCUACCGACACUGCAGCAUUGAAACAAUGGAGGUGCCCAGGAGGCGAUUUUCUGACCUCACCAAAUCUCUGCAAGAGUGCAGAAUCCCCCACAAGUCUGUGCUGGGCAUCUCACUGGAAGAUGGGGAAGGGUGGCCCUGAGUCCACAGCCACCCAGCUGAGGUCCUGGGUCUCUGAGCAAAGGAGCAUGCUUGGGCGUUGUGGCCUCUUAGGCAGCCUGUUUCAAGUGCCAUGUGGACCUGGUGCAGCUGGGAAGCUUGGGACUCUCGUCUGCACUGCGUGUCCUCUGAAGCAGUGAAGUCUGUGCCUAUGCCGAGCGCGCUAAGAAGUCUCCCUUCCAGCUGUUCCAUUCUCUCCACCACCAGCGUAACUGGCAAGUUACCAAGGUUGUUCCUGAAACAGCAGUGAUCAUGACUUCUCCUUUCCAGAGUUUUGGGUCCUUCUGAAUUAAUGGUCCUUUUCGAACACCGGCUUGCCUUUACAGUGAACUGUGAUUCUCUCGAAGCCAAUGCUUUCCUGUCUGUAUUUGAUGCAGGAUUAAACACUUCCCAGAGAGGAUUCUAGUCUGGUAAAUAACCACAGUGUAGGAACUAUCUAACUGGCAUUUGUGUUUCUUGCGAGUAUUUUGAAGAAACAGGCCGUUGACCCCAUCUUUGGAAGUAGCCCUUUACCAUGCAUGGUCAGUUUCUUAGGGAUUUACUAUUUGUGUGAGGUGGCAUCUAAGGGAAGAAUGGGUUUUCUUCCCCAAAACAUCAGCAUUUCUAAAAUAGUCCUAAAGCUUGAAAGUAAGUUGCUUCCAUGAGCAUGGAUUACCCAGUAGCUACUUUUUAAUAGAGACUGACUAGGUUUACAACUUCUGGGAGCUACUCUGUGGGCUGAAUUCUUCCAAAACCGAGAAAAGCCAGUGCAGUCUGAUUUCUUUUGCUUUUGUCAGUAAUGGAAUCUUUUGUUUUUAAAAUGUACAAACCUAUAAGUUUAAACAGGUUUGUACUGACAACCUCCUUGGCUUAUUUGGGGGUGGAGCAAUUGUUUUAUUCCCCAGUUUCAGUGCGUUGCCCACUUCAAACAUGGUGUGUCCUUUGGAGCUGUGACAGAGGUGCCUGUUCUGACUUAGAACCUCUGGAGGAGGAGGGGGGUGCCUUGGUCUCGUGUUACUUUGCUGUGCCUGUGCUGAGAGACCAUGUGCCCGAGCAUCUGGUUGACCGGCAUGAAGUACAUCAGCCUGUCUUAGCCUGAGCUGCUUUGAAGACCAUGGGGUCUUGUGUUUCCAACUUCGAAGUGCUGAUGUGGACAGUUUGCCAAUGUUCUCUUCUAUUGCAAGUUCAGCCAGACUCCAUGACUCAUCUGAUCCCUUUUAUGGCCAAAUCAUCCUUCAGAGUAGGGAACACUCAGACAUUCUGUGCAUGUUGUUCCCCCAAAGCAUGGUCAUCACAAAGUCCUGAGUUCUGGUGUGUGCUCCCGCCUCCUGGGUAUACAGAGAGAAGGCAGGAAUCAGGAGUUCCAGAAGCAUAUACAUGUGGCUACCCCAGCAACAAGCGCAUCCUGUGCUCAGAUAAGCUGCAUGGUUGGGAGUGUUUUUUCUCGCACGUUGAGGCUUAGUGGAGAUGGGCACCACUGCCAUUUGCUCAGAAGAAGGCUGGUCUGGUCCUAACUGCAUCCCACACUGCCCAGAUCAUUCUAGAAUAGGUUAUUUCUGAAUGUUUUAUAGAAUUUCUUAAUACCAUCCUGGUUUGGUCAGCCAUUCCUUUGAUUGGAAAGGUCAGCUGGGGCCAGUGGUGCCUCAGGCAGGCCCACACAACUGGCCACCUCUUCCCGUUAAUGACCACAGCAGACAGAAUUUGAGCCCAGCACCUAAAAGUACAGGAAUUUCACUUCCCACCAGGACUUGAGCACAUAACUCUAUGUCUGAUCUAGGAGGCUGGGGGAAGAGCCUCCCAUAAAAUCACACCUACUCUGUGGUAAGAAUAAAAUCCCACCCACCUGGGACUUGGUAAUUUCUCCAGACAGGAAAGCUUUAGAAAACUUGAGUGAAAUGGAGCAAGCUUGAAGGAGUUAGAAUCUUCUGUGCUUAGGGUUUGCUGCUGCUGGUGAGCUUAGAAUUUUGGGGUUGGGAAAAAGUGGAAGGCAUAAGCAUAGAAAUAUUUUAGGAUAUUUUAGGAUAUGUGAAUAAAGCUAGACUCAAACCAUCAUAAUAAACAUUUUUUUUUUGGACAAAAGAUGAUACGAUAAAAACCAACUUGUGUGAAACUGAGUCAGUGGAGAAGUGCAUCUCGUAUUUUAACCUAAGGCUUCAGCUCCCACACACGACUGGACAGAGGGGUGUGUUAGCCUGAUCUUCAGUUUUCUCAUUGGGAAAGCACUUGUUCCACUGUUAGAACCAAGUCCUCCUCCCCGGACACUUCUGAUGCCCACUGCAGAAGCGACGGGGCUCCUGCUCUCAGCUUCUGUCACAGCACUUAGCUUGUCUGGAUAAGAGUCACCUGAAUUUUUCCUAAACAUCAUUCCAAGUACUCUGAUUUUGGGGAUUGGCAAGAACAAACUAAAUCAGAAUUCAGAGUUCCUGAUGGCUCCACAUGUUGCAUUGCAGCUGAGGCCCCCUGUCCUAAAUGGGCUCAACCGGCCUAGCACACUCCUCUUGGUGGCUUUGGGUGGGUCAGCCUUGCCCAGUUUGGGGUCAUAGACCUCAGUUAUUCAUUUAACCGAUGGCCAUUGAGGGCUUACCCAGUGCCACACUUUGAGACAAGCAUGGGUGUCCUGAAAAGAAAGUGUUGGCAAGAAAACAUGAACCCACCAUUGGACUCUCAACUCAAACCUUACUGAAGUCAGUGGCUAUAGCUUUAUCUGCAAAGGACCCCAAAGUGAGGAUCCCACAUUGUUACUGCUGGCUCUUCAUCCCACCCUCUGGAGAUGCUAAGGAAGCUCUUGCCCACCUUUUCUAGUGAUGGAGUAGGAACUUUGCAUAGGACAAACCUUCAUGAUAGGUUACUCUAGUAUAUUCCCUCAUAAAGUCCAAUAGGUAAAUUAGUCUUGGCAGCAGAAGGAACAGCAGGAGAAGUAAGUGAUUCAUCAUCUAGAAUCCAGAAAAUUUGCACCAACAGAUGGCAGGUGGUUAUAACACAACAGAUCUUGCCCUGAGAAUAUCUGGGGACCCAGCCAACAGCCUUCAAGGCAGGGCACUCCUGCGGAAGAGAUGGCUUGUGAACAUGACUGUGGACCCAGAGUCACCCCAGAGCUCCCAUAUAAAAUGCUUCACAGAGAAACUAAGAGCAGCCUUGGGGCAUUCAUUCCAAUUAAUAACCUUAAAGACUAGAGCCAGAUCCACCUGCAUUACAAAAGCAGGCAUUCGAGGAACUAAACUUUGCUUUUGUUCAUGCUCUUACCUGCCGUUUUAAAUGGGUUUCUAAUGUCAAAUAAAGCCACCCUGCCUCUUGGGACAAAGAUGUUUCUCUUUACUUAGUUUUAAAAAUAAAAUCCUCAUAAUAAGUUCGGAUAAAAGAGACUUUUACAUGGUAAGAGGAUCUACUUUUCUACCUUUUAAACGGAAUAAAGAAGACAGCUAUAUUAUUUUGCUUUAGCAUUAGUUUAGAAGUCAUUCCAAGAAUUAAGCAGGAACAUCUGUUUUCUCAGUCCAUUAAGGCAACACCCCACAGUAAAGUUAAAAGUUCACGAGCCUAUUGACUCUCAUCCAGAAACCAGAACCAACCAAACCCCACCAUAUAACAGGGAAGGCCUGAGGUCGCUUCGGAGGAGUUAGCAAUCAAAGGAGAACAGACUUUUGGUGACUCAGUUACCAACACACAACACUCAUAAAACUAAAAUUAGGUGUUUUAUUUUUUGUCUACACGGGUGGCGUGCCACUUUCCUUUCCUGAUUAGGGAAGCUUCUCCCAGCCCUUUCUGACGUUCAUCUGUGUGCCUUUAUGUUCAAACAGUUUAGGAAGCAGCAGCCCUCCUAACAGUCGACGCGGAAGCACAAAUCUCUGGAGGUAUUUUUGGACACACUUAAAUCCUAUCCCAAGAGACUGAACGACUGUGGUGACAAAUGCCCACGGGUAAAACUGAGCAAGCCUCAUUCAGACUGUCCUGCUCAGAGGCGCCCUCUGGCUGCCGUGUUGAGGGGCUGGGGUGGAAGAUGGAAGACUUGAGUGCUGGAGGUAUGAAGGUGACCAGAGAGAGGUGAUGGUGGUUCGGGCCAGGGUGGUAGCCAGAGAUGUCAUGAGAGGUGGCCAGAUUCUGGACAUAUAAUCCAUUUUCUUAAGGAGAAAAAAAAGGAUAGUUUGACAAGUUGGGAUUCACCCAGGUGGACUUAGCUUGACCAAUAUCGCCAACGUGGAUUGUUUCUGCAAAAACAAACAAGCAAACAACCACCACGGCAGCAAAGCACAUGGCAGGCAGGGGAAAGACACUGACCAGCAGGAACAUUCCCAUCAAGGAAAUGCACGAGUGUUUUUGGACAAAGUGUACAGAGAAAAUCAAAGCUAUUCAUUGUUUUAAUUAAGAGAUAAAACUAAGGUCACUGUUUCACUUAAUGUUGAGAUAUAAGUUAAAAGUAUCAUCUACCUCUAGGGGUAUGAUAUGACUGCUGACCAAGGUUACUUAAUAAGAAAUCCUUGUUCUAGUUAAAUACACUGUUUAUCUCUAUCUCCUGUCCUUCAUCCCUCCCUUUCUUGCCACCCUUCCCUCCAUUUAUUCCAGUCCAGCAGCUGACUGGGGAUGCAUUUCUUCUUGGGAAGGCAAACAAAGCCAUCAUUCUGGGGCUUAAUUAAUAAAGCUCCUAGUUUCAUAGUU